GCCACACACACAGCGAGCGGGCGGGCAGAAGGCGGUUCUGCUGGUCUCCUCUUCCUGCUGCAGCCAGCCCAGCGUGCGGGCCAUGGGCCCUGCCGGCGGGUGAGGCAGCCGCGUGGCAGGCAUGUUCGGAGGCCCGGGGCCUGGGGUCCUGGGAGCCCAGGGCAUGGCGGGACCCCUGCGGGGCCGGGUGGAAGAGCUGAAGCUGCCGUGGUGGCGGGAGAGCUCACCGCUGGUGCUGCGGCACAGCGAGGCGGCUCGGCUGGCGGCCGACGCCCUCCUGGAGCGGGGUGAGGCUGCCUACCUGCGGGUCAUCUCCGAGGAGCGGGAGCUGCCCUUCCUGAGCGCCCUGGAUGUGGACUACAUGACCAGCCAUGUGCGCGGGGGCCCUGAGCUCAGCGAGGCUCAGGGGCAGGAGGCCUCCGGGCCAGACCGCCUCAGCCUGCUCUCUGAAGUCACCUCAGGGACUUACUUCCCCAUGGCCUCUGACAUAGACCCCCCAGACCUGGACCUGGGCUGGCCCGAGGUGCCACAGGCCACAGGCUUCAGCCCCACCCAGGCUGUGGUCCACUUCCAGAGGGACAAGGCCAAGAACAUCAAGGACCUGCUGCGCUUCCUUUUCAGCCAGGCCCACACGGUGGUGGCUGUGGUGAUGGACAUAUUCACUGACAUGGAGCUUCUGUGUGACCUCAUGGAGGCCUCAAGCCGGCGUGGUGUCCCUGUGUACCUGCUCCUUGCCCAGGAGCACCUGAGGCACUUCCUGGAGAUGUGCUACAAGAUGGACCUCAAUGGGGAGCACCUGCCGAACAUGCGUGUGCGGAGCACGUGUGGGGACACAUACUGCAGCAAGGCUGGCCGCCGCUUCACGGGGCAGGCCCUGGAGAAGUUCGUCCUCAUUGACUGUGAGCAAGUGGUGGCGGGCAGUUACAGCUUCACCUGGCUUUGCAGCCAGGCCCACACUAGCAUGGUGCUGCAGCUGAGGGGCCGCAUCGUGGAAGACUUUGACCGGGAGUUCCGCUGUCUGUACGCUGAGUCGCAGCCUGUGGAGGGCUUCUGUGGCGGUGAGGACCCGCUGUCUCCCCGGGCACUGCGUCCUCCCCCUGUGGCCCUAGCCUUCAGGCCUGAUGUCCCAAGCCCCACGUCGUCCCUGCCCUCCAGCACCAGCCUCAGCAGCAUCAAGCAGUCACCGCUUAUGGGUCGCUCCUCCUACCUCGCUCUACCAGGAGGUGGUGAUUGCAGUGAUACGGGUGUGGUGUCCUCGUCCCUGGGUCCUGCCCGCCGUGAGGCCAGUGGCCAGCCCUCCCUACAUCGCCAACUGUCAGACCCUAACCACGGCUCCCCUCCUGGGCUCUAUAGGGCCAAUCUCGGCAAGCUAGGGGCAUACCCAUGGUCCCAGUCCUCCCCUGCCCUCAACCAUAAUAGUACCAGCCCCUUAACCUUGGCAGUGGGGUCACCUCUGCUUCCUCGCUCCCGGCCCCUCCUCCAGUUCCAUCGGGGUGCCCCAGCUCUGUCCCGGUUCCCAGAGAAUGGGCUCCCAGGAAGCCAAGAGCCCAGCCCCCUGCGGGGUCGAUGGGUACCUGGCACAACCCUGGAGACAGUGGAGGAGAAGGAGAAGAAGGCAUCUCCAAGUCAGAGCCGUGGCCAGCUGGAUCUCCUUGUCCCCUUCCCCAGAGCCCGAGAAGUGGGAGACCCUGACUCUGGGGUUACCCCCAACUCAGGCCCCCUUCGGCCUGGCGAGCAGGCCCCAGAGGACAGGAGGUUGUCCCCAAGCCAGGCCGACAGCCAGCUGGAUCUCCUGUCCCGAGCCCUGGGUACUGGGGGUGCCCCUGAGUUGGGUUCCCUCAGACCUGGUGAUCGGGCCCUGGAGGACAGGAGGCUGUCCCUAAACCAAAGCCGUGGCCAAUCAGACCUCCUGAUGCAGUACCCCAAGGCCCAGGGUUCCAGAGUGCCCCUUGAAACCAACUCCUCAGCCAGACCUGCCAGACGGGCACCAGAUGAGCGGCGGCAGACCCUGGGGCACAGCCAGCUGGACCUCAUCACAAAGUUCGGCCCAUUCCGUGGUGAGGGGCCUGGGCCCAAUGGUCUCCCGAUAUCAAGCCCUGCUCGCACGGCUGGAGCUGGGUCUGGGGAUGAGAAACGGCUAACCCUGGGCCACAGCAAGCUGGACCUCAUCACCAAGUAUCAUCAGUUGCACGGGGCCAGGCAGGGAACUGAGCCUGGGGGUCCCAAGGGUGGCCAUCUCAAUGGUGGUAACAGUGACCUGGUCAGGGAUGAGAAACGGCUGACCCUGGGUCACAGCAAACUGGACCUCAUCACUAAGUACAACAAGUCCAAGUUCAAGCAGCUCCGAAGCCGCUUUGAGUCCUAGCCAAAGGACUGGCAUCGGGGGUGCACUGGCAAGGGCAGGCCCCUCCUCUGUCCACCGAGACUCUGGACUUGCUCAGGUCCCAGACUGGGGAAGGGAGGUGUCUAGAAACCCAGGUCAGACACACUCUCUGGGCUCAAGAUUCUUGUGUACACACACACACACACACACACACACACACACCCUAACUAGUAUCUUCUUGAAUCUAGGCUGUGUUUCCAGCCCUGUGCUGGGCCUGUAGAGCUGACAGGUGGGUCACACUCAGACCUGGGGACAGAGGUGAAAUGCACAAGCUGCUGGAGAAGGGGUCAGAGCCAUAUCAAGUUAAAGGUUAACCAGUUACAGAGGGUGUUAGAAAACAAAGGGCAGAGAGUCCUGGAGAAGGUGGAGUAGUCAGAAAACUUUCUUAGAGGAGAUGGAGGUGGCCUUUGAGCCAGGCCCUGAAGGAUGGGGAGGUUUUGGACAGAGGGAGGAGAGAGUUAGAAAAAUUUUUGGUAGAGAGAAUCAGGUGAAAGAGAUGCCCUAAAGAGGACUGAGUGGGUCUGAGGUGAAUGAGUGAGGAAGAGCAGAGUAUGUGGAUACCCGGAAACACACACACACACACAUCAUCAUUAUCAUCAUCAUCAUUGUCGUCGUCAUCAUCUUGCUGAGUCAUCAUCAUCAUCAUCAUCAUUGUCGUCGUCAUCAUCUUGCUGAGUGUCUCUUGAAGUACAGGCUGUGACAGGUUGUGGGCCAUUUUCCUGAACUCACCACUUACCCGGGAUAGUAAACAUGAUACACAUCAAUAAAGGCAGACUUUAUUGUGAA